ACUGCCGCGGCCCUGCUGCUCAGGGCACAUGCCUCCCCUCCCCAGGCCGCGGCCCAGCUGACCCUCGGGGCUCCCCCGGCAGCGGACAGGGAAGGGUUAAAGGCCCCCGGCUCCCUGCCCCCUGCCCUGGGGAACCCCUGGCCCUGUGGGGACAUGAACUGUGUUUGCCGCCUGGUCCUGGUCGUGCUGAGCCUGUGGCCAGAUACAGCUGUCGCCCCUGGGCCACCACCUGGCCCCCCUCGAGUUUCCCCAGACCCUCGGGCCGAGCUGGACAGCACCGUGCUCCUGACCCGCUCUCUCCUGGCGGACACGCGGCAGCUGGCUGCACAGCUGAGGGACAAAUUCCCAGCUGACGGGGACCACAACCUGGAUUCCCUGCCCACCCUGGCCAUGAGUGCGGGGGCACUGGGAGCUCUACAGCUCCCAGGUGUGCUGACAAGGCUGCGAGCGGACCUACUGUCCUACCUGCGGCACGUGCAGUGGCUGCGCCGGGCAGGUGGCUCUUCCCUGAAGACCCUGGAGCCCGAGCUGGGCACCCUGCAGGCCCGACUGGACCGGCUGCUGCGCCGGCUGCAGCUCCUGAUGUCCCGCCUGGCCCUGCCCCAGCCACCCCCGGACCCGCCGGCGCCCCCGCUGGCGCCCCCCUCCUCAGCCUGGGGGGGCAUCAGGGCCGCCCACGCCAUCCUGGGGGGGCUGCACCUGACACUUGACUGGGCCGUGAGGGGACUGCUGCUGCUGAAGACUCGGCUGUGACCCGGGGCCCAAAGCCACCACCGUCCUUCCAAAGCCAGAUCUUAUUUAUUUAUUUAUUUCAGUACUGGGGGCGAAACAGCCAGGUGAUCCCCCCGCCAUUAUCUCCCCCUAGUUAGAGACAGUCCUUCCGUGAGGCCUGGGGGGCAUCUGUGCCUUAUUUAUACUUAUUUAUUUCAGGAGCAGGGGUGGGAGGCAGGUGGACUCCUGGGUCCCCGAGGAGGAGGGGACUGGGGUCCCGGAUUCUUGGGUCUCCAAGAAGUCUGUCCACAGACUUCUGCCCUGGCUCUUCCCCAUCUAGGCCUGGGCAGGAACAUAUAUUAUUUAUUUAAGCAAUUACUUUUCAUGUUGGGGUGGGGACGGAGGGGAAAGGGAAGCCUGGGUUUUUGUACAAAAAUGUGAGAAACCUUUGUGAGACAGAGAACAGGGAAUUAAAUGUGUCAUACAUAUCCACUUGAGGGCGAUUUGUCUGAGAGCUGGGGCUGGAUGCUUGGGUAACUGGGGCAGGGCAGGUGGAGGGGAGACCUCCAUUCAGGUGGAGGUCCCGAGUGGGCGGGGCAGCGACUGGGAGAUGGGUCGGUCACCCAGACAGCUCUGUGGAGGCAGGGUCUGAGCCUUGCCUGGGGCCCCGCACUGCAUAGGGCCUUUUGUUUGUUUUUUGAGAUGGAGUCUCGCUCUGUUGCCUAGGCUGGAGUGCAGUGAGGCAAUCUGAGGUCACUGCAACCUCCACCUCCCGGGUUCAAGCAAUUCUCCUGCCUCAGCCUCCCGAUUAGCUGGGAUCACAGGUGUGCACCACCAUGCCCAGCUAAUUAUUUAUUUCUUUUGUAUUUUUAGUAGAGACAGGGUUUCACCAUGUUGGCCAGGCUGGUUUCGAACUCCUGACCUCAGGUGAUCCUCCUGCCUCGGCCUCCCAAAGUGCUGGGAUUACAGGUGUGAGCCACCACACCUGACCCAUAGGUCUUCAAUAAAUAUUUAAUGGAAGGUUCCACAAGUCACCCUGUGAUCAACAGUACCCGUAUGGGACAAAGCUGCAAGGUCAAGAUGGUUCAUUAUGGCUGUGUUCACCAUAGCAAACUGGAAACAAUCUAGAUAUCCAACAGUGAGGGUUAAGCAACAUGGUGCAUCUGUGGAUAGAACGCCACCCAGCCGCCCGGAGCAGGGACUGUCAUUCAGGGAGGCUAAGGAGAGAGGCUUGCUUGGGAUAUAGAAAGAUAUCCUGACAUUGGCCAGGCAUGGUGGCUCACGCCUGUAAUCCUGGCACUUUGGGAGGACGAAGCGAGUGGAUCACUGAAGUCCAAGAGUUCGAGACCGGCCUGCGAGACAUGGCAAAACCCUGUCUCAAAAAAGAAAGAAUGAUGUCCUGACAUGAAACAGCAGGCUACAAAACCACUGCAUGCUGUGAUCCCAAUUUUGUGUUUUUCUUUCUAUAUAUGGAUUAAAACAAAAAUCCUAAAGGGAAAUACGCCAAAAUGUUGACAAUGACUGUCUCCAGGUCAAAGGAGAGAGGUGGGAUUGUGGGUGACUUUUAAUGUGUAUGAUUGUCUGUAUUUUACAGAAUUUCUGCCAUGACUGUGUAUUUUGCAUGACACAUUUUAAAAAUAAUAAACACUAUUUUUAGAAUAACAGAA